UUCAUGCCUCUCUCCCUGGUUCUGCCAUUUCCCCUGUGGGGGGCUGCCCAGGGCCAAACAGGCCAGAGGGCUCCACCAGCCCUGGAAAUUACAGGCUUUGGGAGUAGGGUUGCCAGAUAAAAUAAAAGAUGCCUAGUUAAAAUUGAAUUUCAGGUAAAUAAUUAAUAAUUUUUUUAGUAUAAGUGUAUCCCAAAUACUUCACGGGAGUACCAAACAAUGAUUGACUGUUCACUUGAAAUUCAAGUCCAACUGAGCUUUCUGUAUUUUUAUUUGCUAAGUCUGGCAGCCCUGCUUAGGAGGAGAAACAGGUGUGUCUGUCCCUCCCAACUGGUGAGGACACCUGACAGGGGCCCAGACACCAGAGUGGGACCUGCCUGAUGGAGAGAAGCUUGGGCUUGGUUUAUUUCCCUUUUCAUAAAAAAGCUGCUUUGAGAUGUAAGAGAAUCAUGUUGGUGGAAGAGUGAAGAGGUUGUUUUGGGGGAGGUCUGCCUUACUCUGAGGGAAGAUGGGAAGCGGGGGGAGUGGCCAGCUGUGGAAAUUUGGGGUAGUCCCCUACGUAUCCUGUGCCUCAGUUUCCCCAUGUGUAAACAGGAGUAAUUAUCUCAUCCUGGGGCUGCAGUGAGGAUCAGAUGAGCUAAUGUACAAAAAGGCUUAGGCAGGCCUGCCGUGAUAAGAGUGCAGAGGCUGGGGGCUUUUUAUGUUAUGGUAUUGUUGUUAUUAUUACUCCUGGGGAGGUGGUGGGCAAGAGUGUGGACUGAGGAGCCACAUGGCUGGGUUUGGAUCCCAGCCCGGCCACAGACCUUGGGCAAGUUACUUAACCUCGGCUUUCUCAUCUGUAUAAUGGGAGACAAUAAUAGAUAGUGCCUCCCUUCUAGGGUUAUUGAGAGGAUUGCAUGAUGGGCUGGCACACAGCAUGAGCUCAGUAAGUGUCAGUCACUGUUAUCCCCCAGGGGCAUGCAUGCCGCUGCCUCCAGGAGGCCCUCCAACUCGCAGUGGCCUCUCCCUACAUGGGUUCCCACUGAGCUGUGAUCCUGUGGCCUUGAGCCCCAUCUGGCUGCCCUGGACAAUGUUGGUCCUCAGCUCCCCAGCGGGAUCAACAGUGGGGAGAGCAGUGGGUGGAUCUGCCCGCCAGGCAGUACCUGAGUGCACAGUGGGCACCCCACAGUCAAAGGAUGCAUAGUCUGGUUUCCAAGGAGGAACCCCAGGCUAGGUGGAAUGAGGGAAAUGCAAUCUCAGGGCCAGAUAACAUCACAGAUACUUUAAACCUGCAAUUAAUUUCUGGUUGUUUGACCAAAUCCGGCCAAGUUUCCCGGGUGACACUGCAGAGCUGUGGAACAGCAUGGGCUUGGAGUCAGACCUGUUGCACAUCUGGCUCUGCCAUGUGAUGCAACCUCAGGCUUGUCACGAGGCCUCCUUGAGCCUCAGUUGCUAAUAUGCCAAAUGGGGAUGAUAUUGCUCACCUUACAGCUUGUAAGAGUGGAGGGAGCUGCGUGCGCCAGGUGCCUGGCAUGCAGCGGGCACUCAACCAGAUUGAAUUCCCUUCCCAGGGAAGAAUUCAAGGAUAUCUUCCCACCCACUAAGGAGACAUGUGAUGGGAUCUGGGGUGAGAAUUGCUCUUUUUAAAGCUCUCAGAACUGUAAGGGGCUCCACCCACCAAUGGCUGGUGUUCACUGAGCUCUUCGUGCCCAGACCUGCACUGGGGAUUUAUCGAGCACAUGGCUGGCUUCUGACUUCCGAAGAGCUCGCCAUUCUGGUCAGUGCCUGAGGGCACAGAAAUGUUUGAGGUCUAUGGGACGCCUGGCGUGGACAUCUACAUCUCUCCCAACAUGGAGAGGGGCCGGGAGCGUGCAGACACCAGGCGGUGGCGCUUUGACGCGACUUUGGAGAUCAUCGUGGUCAUGAACUCCCCCAGCAAUGACCUCAACGACAGCCAUGUUCAGAUUUCCUACCACUCCAGCCAUGAGCCUCUGCCCCUGGCCUAUGCGGUGCUCUACCUCACCUGUGUUGACAUCUCUCUGGAUUGCGACCUGAACUGUGAGGGAAGGCAGGACAGGAACUUUGUAGACAAGCGGCAGUGGGUCUGGGGGCCCAGUGGGUAUGGCGGCAUCUUGCUGGUGAACUGUGACCGUGAUGAUCCGAGCUGUGAUGUCCAGGACAAUUGUGACCAGCACGUGCACUGCCUGCAAGACCUGGAAGACAUGUCUGUCAUGGUCCUGCGGACGCAGGGCCCUGCAGCCCUCUUUGAUGACCACAAACUUGUCCUCCAUACCUCCAGCUAUGAUGCCAAACGGGCACAGGUCUUCCACAUCUGCGGUCCUGAGGAUGUGUGUGAGGCCUAUAGGCAUGUGCUGGGCCAAGAUAAGGUGUCCUAUGAGGUACCCCGCUUGCAUGGGGAUGAGGAGCGCUUCUUCGUGGAAGGCCUGUCCUUCCCUGAUGCCGGCUUCACAGGACUCAUCUCCUUCCAUGUCACUCUGCUGGACGACUCCAACGAGGAUUUCUCGGCAUCCCCUAUCUUCACUGACACUGUGGUGUUCCGAGUGGCACCCUGGAUCAUGACGCCCAGCACUCUGCCACCCCUAGAGGUGUAUGUGUGCCGUGUGAGGAACAACACGUGUUUUGUGGAUGCGGUGGCAGAGCUGGCCAGGAAGGCCGGCUGCAAGCUGACCAUCUGCCCACAGGCCGAGAACCGCAACGACCGCUGGAUCCAGGAUGAGAUGGAGCUGGGCUACGUUCAGGCGCCGCACAAGACCCUCCCGGUGGUCUUUGACUCCCCAAGGAAUGGGGAACUGCAGGAUUUCCCUUACAAAAGAAUCCUGGGUCCAGAUUUUGGUUACGUGACUCGGGAACCACGCGACAGGUCUGUGAGUGGCCUGGACUCCUUUGGGAACCUGGAGGUCAGCCCUCCAGUGGUGGCCAAUGGGAAAGAGUACCCCCUGGGGAGGAUCCUCAUUGGGGGCAACCUGCCUGGGUCAAGUGGCCGCAGGGUCACCCAGGUGGUGCGGGACUUCCUCCAUGCCCAGAAGGUGCAGCCCCCCGUGGAGCUCUUUGUGGACUGGUUGGCCGUGGGCCAUGUGGAUGAGUUUCUGAGCUUUGUCCCUGCCCCCGAUGGGAAGGGCUUCCGGAUGCUCCUGGCCAGCCCUGGGGCCUGCUUCAAGCUCUUCCAGGAAAAGCAGAAGUGUGGCCACGGGAGGGCCCUCCUGUUCCAGGGGGUUGUUGAUGAUGAGCAGGUCAAGACCAUCUCCAUCAACCAGGUGCUCUCCAAUAAAGACCUCAUCAACUACAAUAAGUUUGUGCAGAGCUGCAUCGACUGGAACCGUGAGGUGCUGAAGCGGGAGCUGGGCCUGGCAGAGUGUGACAUCAUUGACAUCCCACAGCUCUUCAAGACCGAGAGGAAAAAAGCAACGGCCUUCUUCCCUGACUUGGUGAACAUGCUGGUGCUGGGGAAGCACCUGGGCAUCCCCAAGCCCUUUGGGCCCAUCAUCAAUGGCUGCUGCUGCCUGGAGGAGAAGGUGCGGUCCCUGCUGGAGCCGCUGGGCCUCCACUGCACCUUCAUUGAUGACUUCACUCCAUACCACAUGCUGCAUGGGGAGGUGCACUGUGGCACCAAUGUGUGCAGAAAGCCCUUCUCUUUCAAGUGGUGGAACAUGGUGCCCUGAGACAGCUCCCACCCACCAUCCUGUCCCCCUGGGGCGGGCAUUGGCCCAGGUGGUGGAGACAGAGACAGGCCCCUGAACGAUAAGCACCAAGAGACCCCAAGGCUCCAGAUGGAACACUGAGGGUGACCGUCCCUCUCAGAAGCCUUUUCCCUGGAAGUGUCCAUGCCUCACCUGCAACCCAUGUGGUUCUCAGACUUGAAUCUUCUCGGCCCCCCAAAAAGAAGGACCUCAUUUCUUAUAGCCUCUCCUGUGAUUCAACACAACCCAUGGAGAUGUCCCCUUCUCACUCUGAAAUCAUCCAUUUGGGGACAAAUCCACAUUGGGGUCUAGAAACAUCCACGUAUCUCAUCAGCCAUCUUGUCCUGUGCAUCCUAACAGAGGAAGGAUCCAUGAUUCUGCUUUGGUCCAAUUGCUUCCUCUCUGCAGAGGAACAACCCUAAAACCAGACCACUCCACGCAGGACAGGCAGGAGAGAUUCUUCCUAAAGCCUCCCCCAUAAAAAGGGAGCUGUGGAUCCACUUAGAUCAGGGCGGAACCAUCUUUCACCCGGCCAAGCUCCUGCCCAGAUGUUGACCCUCACCCAGCGUGAGCUGUCACAUAGUAGGAGCUUCUAGAUGCAUGUGGAAGCAAUGAGAGUUGUCCCUUAGCCUUAUAAACUCCCCAUGAUCUGACAUGCAGAAAUCCAGCCUUGUCCAGAAUCCUCCUGGAAUUUCUUGGAGACGAAAGUAUCUGGGGGAUUGUUGGGUACUAGGGAGACUGGGUACAAGGGUGAAAAGUAGUUCCCAUAAUACACAUGGUUGACUAUGGUGAUCCACCUUGUGAUGGUUAAUAUUAGGUGUCUGGAGAAGGUUGCUUCAUUGGCCCUGGGACUUCUCUCUGCAGGAGGAGAGAACGCUGCCUCUCCUCUGGAUUGGUCUCAGGCUCUCUGUUGGCCUUUGGUCAGCGUUUCCACAUCCUGCUCUGCUGCAGGAGAGGGGGCUAAGGGGCUGGAUCCACCAAGGCAGCUCACAGCGGGAAAACUCUGGGAAUGAACCACUGAAUUCAGGGGAUGGGGGUGGGGGGGCGGUUCUCGAGGUGUGUGCCAGCUACACGUGUGUUCUGUAUGGGUCCAGCUGCGUUUCCAUCACUCGCUAAUAAAUCAACAGAAACACAAA